ACGCGCCUGUGUUGCCGCCCGCGGCCCUGGCUUCGGGCUUCAGGGAGCUCUGGUGCAGUCUCCGCCUGUCAGUGCCGGCAGUCGUCCGCGGCGCCCGCCCCGGUCCCGCACUGGUGCAGCCAUGUCCUCUUCCCCGUGGGAGCCUGCGACCCUGCGCCGGGUGUUCGUGGUGGGGGUUGGCAUGACCAAGUUUGUGAAGCCUGGAGCUGAGAAUUCAAGAGACUACCCUGACUUGGCAGAAGAAGCAGGCAAGAAGGCUUUAGCUGAUGCACAGAUCCCUUAUUCAGCAGUGGACCAGGCAUGUGUUGGCUAUGUUUUUGGUGACUCUACCUGUGGGCAGAGGGCUAUCUAUCACAGUUUGGGAAUGACUGGAAUUCCUAUAAUCAAUGUCAACAAUAACUGUGCUACUGGUUCUACUGCUUUGUUUAUGGCCCGCCAGCUGAUUCAGGGUGGUGUGGCAGAAUGUGUCUUGGCUCUUGGGUUUGAGAAGAUGAGUAAGGGAAGCCUUGGAAUAAAAUUUUCAGAUAGAACCAUUCCCACUGAUAAGCAUGUUGACCUCCUGAUCAAUAAGUAUGGAUUGUCUGCUCACCCAGUUGCUCCUCAGAUGUUUGGGUAUGCUGGAAAAGAACAUAUGGAAAAAUAUGGAACAAAAAUUGAACACUUUGCAAAAAUUGGAUGGAAAAAUCAUAAACAUUCAGUUAAUAACCCGUAUUCCCAGUUCCAAGAUGAAUACAGUUUAGAUGAAGUGAUGGCAUCUAAAGAAGUUUUUGAUUUUUUGACUAUCUUACAAUGUUGUCCCACUUCAGAUGGUGCUGCAGCAGCAAUUUUGGCCAGUGAAGCAUUUGUACAGAAGUAUGGCCUGCAAUCCAAAGCUGUGGAAAUUUUGGCACAAGAAAUGAUGACUGAUUUGCCAAGCUCGUUUGAAGAAAAAAGCAUUAUUAAAAUGGUUGGCUUUGAUAUGAGUAAAGAAGCUGCAAGAAAAUGCUAUGAGAAAUCUGGCCUGACACCAAAUGAUAUUGACGUAAUAGAACUUCACGAUUGCUUUUCUACCAACGAACUCCUUACUUAUGAAGCACUGGGACUCUGUCCAGAAGGACAAGGUGCAACGCUGGUUGAUAGAGGAGAUAAUACAUAUGGAGGAAAGUGGGUCAUAAAUCCUAGUGGUGGACUGAUUUCAAAGGGACACCCACUAGGCGCUACAGGUCUUAAGAAUUUGGGUGAAAAUGAUGUGAGAAGAAGUGGAAUUUUAACCAAGGGACCGAGCAUUUUCAAAUCAAACCAUGGCUUAUCUCGUCUACUCUGUAAGAGGUUGCCAAAAUAAAUCCUAGGACGAUGACUGGUAAGGCCUAAAUCCAAUAUAAACUCUUAAAAAGCCAGCAAGUCAGUAAGAGCUAAUUAGCUUUUCACCAAAAUUUCUUUUUUACCUUUCAUCAUAUCCUCCAGGCCACCCAUCCUUGUUUCCAUUGCCCAGAGUUUUGCAUUUUUACCACUGCAAUGUGAGGAGAGGUAAAUUUUAUCAUUAAACUCUAUCUGUGCCAGGACAAAUGGAGCCCAGGAGAUGGUGUCUACUCUAGAUACCUGUUGCUAGCUAGAGAUAACUAGGAGAAAGCCCUGAAUUUCUGUUUCUAUUUCUUUUCUUUUUUUAUUUUUGAAACCAGGAUUUCGCUCUGUUGCUCUGGCUGGAGUGCAGUGGCAUGAUCAUGGCUCAUUGUAGCCUCGAUUUCUUGGGCUCAAAUGAUUCUACUAUCUCAGUCUCCCAAGUAGUUGGGACUGCAGGCACGCACCUUCAUACCUGGCUAAUUUUUUACAUUUUUGGUAGAGACGGGCUUUCGCCAUGUUGCUUAGGCUGGUCUCGAACUCCUGGGAUAAAGCAAUCUGCCCAUGUUGGCUUUCCAAAGUGCUGAGAUUAUAGGCAUGAGCCAUCAUGCCUUCUUUUUCUUUUUUUGAGAUAGAGUCUUCCUCUGUUGCCCAGGCUGAAGUGCAGUGCAAACAUGGUGCAAACAUGCUUACUGCAGUCUCUACUUCCUGGGCUCAAGUGAUCCUCCCGCCUCAGUCUCCCAAGUAGCUGGGACCACAGGUGCACACCAUCAUGCCCAGCUAAUUUUAUUUUAUUUUUUCUUUUGUAGAGAUGGGGUCUCCCUAUGCUUCCCAGGCUGGUCUCAAACUCCUGGGCUCAAGUGGUCCUCUCUCCUUGGCCUCCCCAAAAGCUGGGAUUACAGGCGUGAGUCACCACACCCAGCCCCUUUUUCUUUCUUCACAAUUUCACGGAUAGAAAAUUCAUUGUUACUGUAGAUCUUAGCAACCUCAGCAUGCCAUUUUUUUCCCUUAAAGUUGGGAACUUCCACCUUUUCAUUUAAAGGAAGCACUUGUAUGCACAUCUGAAUCGCCACUUCACUCCUCUUGCGCUUUGGGGCCAUCAUUAAGUAAACUAAGGAUGACUUGAACACGAGCAGUACCCAUCACAGUACCCAUCACAGUCAUUCUAAUAACAAAGAUAGCUACUAACUGACUAACGGGUGGGUGGGAUGUACCACUUGGAUAUGCUGGGCAAAGGGAUGAUUCACAUCCCAGGUGGGGUGGAGCUGAAUGGUGCGAGAUUUUAUCAUGCUACUCAGAACAGCAUGCAACUUAAAACUUAUGAAUUGUUUAUUUCUGGCAUUUUCUAUUCAAUAUUUUUAGACUGUAAUCGACUGAGGGUAACUGAAACUGUGGAAAGUGAAACCAUGGAUGUGAGGGCACUACUGUAUUUUACUUUUUUUUGAAAUAUAUUUUACAUGUGAUAGAUAAUUUUGUCAGGCCUCUGAGCCCAAGCUAAGCCAUCAUAUCCCCUGUGACCUGCACGUAUACAUCCAGAUGGCCUGAAGCAACUGAAGAUCCACAAAAGAAGUGAAAAUAGUCAGUUCCUGCCUUAACUGAUGACAUGCCACCAUUGUGAUCUGUUCCUGCCCCACUCUAACUGAUCAAUUGACUUUGUGACAAUACAUCCUCCCCACCCUUGCGAUAAUGUAUUUUGUGAUAUUCACCGCCCUUGUGAAUGUACUUUGUAGGGUAUACCCUCCCUGCCUUUAAGAAGGUUCCAAGAUGGCCAAAUAGGAGCAGCUCCAGUCUACAGCUCCCAGCGUGAGUGACGCAGAAGAUGGGUGAUUUCUGCAUUUCCAACUGAGGUACCAGGUUCAUCUCACUGGGGCUUGUCGGACAGUGGGUGCAGUCCACGGAGUAUGAGCUGAAGCAGGGCAGGGCAUUGCCUCACCCGGGAAGUGCAAGAGGUUGGGGAAUUCCCUUUCCUAGCCAAGGGAAGCCGUGACAGAUGGUACCUGGAAAAUUGGGACACUCCCACCCUAAUACUGCGCUUUUCCAAUGGUCUUAGCAAAUGGCACACCAGGAGAUUAUAUCCCAUGCCUGGCUUGGAGGGUCCCACACCCAUGGAGCCUCGCUUGCUGCUAGCACAGCAGUCUGAGAUUAAACUGCAAGGUGACAGCGAGGCUUGGGGAGGGGCAUCCGCCUUUGCUGAGGCUUGAGUAGGUAAACAAAGUGGCUGGGAAGCUUGAACUGGGUGGAGCCCAUCGCAGCUCAACGAGGCCCGCCUGCCUCUGUAGACUCCACUUCUUGGGGCAGGGCAUAGCUGAACAAAAGGCAGCAGAAACUUCUGCAGACUUAAACGUCCCUGUCUGACAGCUUUGAAGAGAGUAAUGGUUCUCCCAGCAUGGAGUUUGAGAUCUGAGAAUGAACAGAUUGCCUUAAGUGGGUCCCUGACCCCCGAGUAGCCUAACUGGGAGACACCUCCCAGUAGGGGCUGACCAACACCUCAUACAGCCGGGUGUCCCUCUGAGAUGAAGCAUCCAAGGGAAGGAUCAGGCAGCAACAUUUGCUGUUCUGCAAUAUUUGGUGUUCUGCAGUCUCCGCUGGUGAUACCCAGGCAAACAGGGUCUGGAGUGGACCUCCAGCAAACUCCAACAGACCUGCAGCUGAGGGUCCUGACUGUUAGAAGGAAAAUUAACAAACAGAAAGGACAUUCACACCAAAACCCCAUCUGUACGUCACCAUCAUCAAAGACCAAAGGUAGAUAAAUCCACAAAGAUGAGGAGAAACUAGAGCAGAAAAGCUGAAAAUUCUAAAAAUCAGAGUGCCUCUUCCCUCCAAAGGAGCACAGCUCCUCACCAGCAAUGGAACAAAUUUGGACGCAGAGUGACUUUGAUGAGUUGAGAGAAGAAGGCUUCAGAUGAUCGGUAAUAACAAACUUCUCUGAGCUAAAGGAGGAUGUUCAAACCCAUCGCAAAGAAGCUAAAAACCUUGAAAAAAAGAUUAGACGAAUGGCUAAUUAGAAUAAACAGCAUAGAGAAGACCUUAAAUGACCUGAUGGAGCUGAAAACCAUGGCACAAGAACUAUGUGACACAUGCCAAAGCUUCAGUAGCCGAUUUGAUCAAGUGGAAGAAAGGGUAUCAGUGAUUGAAGAUCAAAUGAAUGAAAUGAAGUGAGAAGAGAAGUUCAGAGAAAAAAGAAUAAAAAGAAAUGAACAAAGCCUCCAAGAAAUAUGGGACUAUGUGAAAAGACCAAAUCUACGUCUGACUGGUGUACCUGAAAGUGAGGGGGAGAAUGGAACCAAGUUGGAAAACACUCUUCAGGAUAUUAUCCAGGAGAACUUCCCCAACCUAGCAAGGCAGGCCAACAUUCAAAUUCAGGAAAUACAUAGAACGCCACAAAGAUACUCCUCGAGAAGAGCAACUCCAAGACACGUAAUUGUCAGAUUCACUAAAGUUGAAAUGAAGGAAAAAAUAUUAAGGGCAGCCACAGAGAAAGGUCGGGUUACCCACAAAGGGAAGCCCAACAGACUAACAGCGGAUCUCUCGGCAGAAACUCUACAAGCCAGAAGAGAGUGGGGGCCAAUAUUCAACAUUCUUAAAGAAAAGAAUUUUCAACCCAAAAUUUCAUAUCCAGCCAAACUAAGCUUCAUAAGUGAAGGAGAAAUAAAAUCCUUUACACACAGGCAAAUGCUGAGAGAUUUUGUCACCACCAGGCCUGCCUUACAAGAGCUCCUGAAGGAAGUACUAAACAUGGAAAGGAACAACUGGUACCAGCCACUGAAAAAACAUGCCAAAUUGUAAAGAUCAUUGAUGCUAGGAAGAAACUGCAUCAACUAAUGAGCAAAAUAACCAGCUAACAUCAUAAUGACCAGGAUCAAAUUCACACAUAACAAUAUUAACCUUAAAUGUAAAUGGGCUAAAUGCUCCAAUUAAAAGACACAGACUGGCAAAUUGGAUAAAGAGUCAAGACCCAUCAGUGUGCUGUAUUCAGGAGACCCAUCUCACGUGCAGAGACACACAUAGGCUCAAAAUAAAGGGAUGGAGGAAGAUCUACCAAGCAAAUGGAAAACAAAAAAAAGCAGGGGUUGCAAUCCUAGUCUCUGAUAAAACAGACUUUAAACCGACAAAGAUCAAAAGAGACAAAGAAGGCCAUUACAUAAUGAUAAAGGGAUCAAUUCAACAAGAAGAGAUAACUAUCCUAAAUAUAUAUUCACCCAAUACAGGAGCACCCGGAUUCAUAAAGCAAGUCCUUAGAGACCUACAAAGAGAAUUAGACUCCCACACAAUAAUAAUGGGAGACUUUAAUACCCCACUGUCAACAUUAGAUCAACGAGAGAGAAAGUUAACAAGGAUAUCCAGGACUUGAACUCAGCUCUGCACCAAGUGGCCUUAAUAGACAUCUACAGAACUCUCCACCCCAAAUCAACAGAAUAUAUAUUCUUCUCAGCACCACAUCACACUUAUUCCAAAAUUGACCAUGUAGUUGGAAGUAAAGCACUCCUCAGCAAAUGUAAAAGAACAGAAAUUAUAACAAACUGUCUCUCAGACCAUAGUGCAAUCAAACUAGAACUCAGGAUUAAGAAACUCACUCAAAACCGCUCAACUACAUGGAAACUGAACAGCCUGCUCCUGAAUGACUACUGGGUACAUAAUGAAAUGAAGGAAGAAAUAAAGAUGUUCUUUGAAGCCAAUGAGAACAAAGACACAACAUACCAGAAUCUCUGGGAAACAUUUAAAGCAGUGUGUAGAGGGAAAUUUAUAGCACUAAAUGUACACAAGAGAAAGCAGGAAAGAUCUAAAAUUGACACCCUAACAUCACAAUUAAAAGAACUAGAGAAGCAAGAGCAAACACAUUCAAAAGCUAGCAGAAGGCAAGAAAUAACUAAGAUCAGAGCAGAACUGAAGGGGAUAGAGACACAAAAAAACCCUUCAAAAAAUCAAUGAAUCCAGGAGCUGGUUUUUUGAAGCGAUCAACAAAAUUGAUAGACCGCUAGCAAGACUAAUACAGAAGAAAA